GACCGCGCUCCUGUAGAGGGAAGAAACAAGGUGGCGGUUGAAGGCGAUCUUGAGUGGGGCCCCAGCAAUUCGGUUGAGCCUUCUCCCUCCACUCGCUUCCGCCGGCCGGGCCCCUCCCGCCCAGCCCCUCGGGCCUCCCAACCCGGCCCCGGCGCUCCCCACCGCCGCCACUGCGCCCGGCCCUCCCCGUCAGCUUUCCCUUCUCCCGCCGCCUGGGCUCCAACAAGAGGGGCCGGCGGGGCAGGCCGACCAAGCAGCCCGCGGCUCCCGCUGCGGAGCGCUGCGCCCCGGCCCCGCCGCCGCCGCCGCCCACGUCCGGACCCAUCGGGGGCUCCCCUCGCCGAUACGCGGUAGUAGCCGGGGCAGGUGGGCAGCCGCCAGGCUGAGGUGGCGCCCAAGACGCGGCUGAGCUCGCCCAGGGUGGGCAGCAGUAGCCGGAGGAAGCCACCGCCGCCGGCCCGCCCCGCGCCGGCACCAGCGCACGGGCCCGGCGGGGGCGCGGGGGCAGCCACCUAGCCCGGACCACCGCAGCCCGGAGGGCUGUCAACAGAGUGGUGUAUGAUGACUACGAGAGCGAGGAGGAGGAGUAAGAGGAGGGGGGCGGCGAUGCCGAGGAGACCCAGGAGUCUGAGGACAACUAGGAGGAUGACAUGGAGGAGGACGACGAUGACUCCGAUUAUCCGGAGGAGCUGGAAGAUGACGACGAGGACGCCAGUUACUCCACGGAAAGCAGCUUCAGCAGCACUCCAGAAAGUGGUAAAAUAGCUGUGGAGUGCAGACCCAGUGAAGAGAUUGUAGAUGUCAGAUGGGAAGAACUACACAGUUUAAUUCAAGUCAGUUGCUCUCCCCUGAAGGAAGAGUAUUCUCGGAUUUCACCUCAGAGGAGGAAGAAUUCAGGCUGCCAGAACUGGACUAGCACUUCUGAAGAUCCCAAGGCCAGAUGUCAGCCCUGCCUCAGGAACCAACUGAAAAUUUGGCUCCAUUCCUGAAGGAAUUGGAUUCAGCUGGAGAGCUGCCCCUGGGGCCAGAGCCGUUCUUGGCUGCACAUCAGGACUUAAAUGACAAGCGGACUCCAGAAGAAAGGCUCCCAGAGGUGGUUCCGCUUCUCAACCGGGAUCAGAACCAGGCCCUAGUUCAGCUUCCUCGCCUCAAGUGGGUUCAAACUACAGAUCUAGAUCGGGCUGCAGGUCAUCAGGCAGAUGAAAUACUUGUUCCACUAGACAGUAAGGUUUCAAGACCAACCAAAUUUGUUGUUUCGCCCAAGAACCUGAAGAAAGAUCUAGCUGAACGUUGGAGCCUUCCUGAGAUUGUUGGGAUUCCACACCAAUUAUCCAAACCUCAGCGUCAGAAACAGACUUUGCCAGAUGAUUAUUUGAGUAUGGACACACUGUAUCCCGGCAGCCUACCUCCAGAACUCCGGGUGAACGCAGAUGAGCCUCCAGGGCCUCCUGAGCAAGUUGGACUUUCUCAAUUCCAUCUAGAGCCCAAAAGUCAAAAUCCAGAGACCCUUGAAGACAUCCAGUCCUCUUCACUCCAGGAAGAAGCCCCAGCGCAGCUUCUACAGCUCCCUCAGGAGGUAGAACCUUCAACCCAGCAGGAGGCCCCAGCUCUGCCUCCAGAGUCCUCUAUGGAGAGUCUAGCUCAAACUCCACUGAAUCAUGAAGUGACAGUUCAACCUCCAGGUGAGGAUCAAGCUCAUUAUAAUUUGCCCAAGUUUACAGUCAAACCUGCAGAUGUGGAGGUUACCAUGACUUCAGAGCCUAAAAAUGAGACAGAAUCUACCCAAGCCCAGCAGGAGGCCCCAAUUCAGCCUCCCGAGGAGGCGGAACCUUCUUCUACAGCCCUGAGGACUACAGAUCCUCCUCCAGAACACCCUGAGGUGACACUUCCACCUUCAGACAAGGGUCAGGCUCAGCAUUCACACCUGACUGAAGCCACAGUUCAACCUCUGGACCUGGAGCUUAGCAUAACUACAGAGCCUACUACAGAGGUUAAACCGUCUCCAACCACGGAGGAAACCUCAGCUCAGCCUCCAGACCCGGGGCUUGCCAUAACUCCAGAACCCACUACAGAGAUUGGACAUUCCACAGCCCUGGAGAAGACUAGAGCUCCUCAUCCAGACCAGGUUCAGACUCUGCAUCGAAGCCUGACUGAAGUCACAGGUCCACCUACAAAGUUAGAAUCUUCGCAGGAUUCAUUGGUGCAGUCUGAAACUGCACCAGAGGAACAGAAGGCCUCCACAAGCACCAACAUAUGUGAGCUCUGCACCUGCGGAGAUGAGACUCUGUCAUGUGUUGGUCUCAGCCCAAAGCAGAGGCUCCGCCAAGUGCCUGUGCCAGAGCCCGACACCUACAAUGGCAUCUUCACCACCUUAAAUUUCCAAGGAAACUAUAUUUCAUACCUUGAUGGAAAUGUAUGGAAAGCAUACAGUUGGACCGAGAAACUAAUUCUCAGUGAAAAUUAUUUGACUGAAUUACCUAAGGAUUCAUUUGAAGGCCUGCUAUACCUCCAGUAUUUAGAUUUAUCCUGCAAUAAAAUACGAUAUAUUGAAAGACAAACAUUUGAAUCACUACCAUUUUUGCAGUAUAUAAAUCUGGGCUGCAAUUUAAUUACAAAACUGAGCCUUGGAACAUUUCAGGCCUGGCACGGAAUGCAGUUUUUACACAACUUAAUUCUCAAUCGCAAUCCUCUGACUACUGUCGAAGAUCCAUAUCUCUUUGAACUGCCGGCAUUAAAAUAUCUAGACAUGGGAACAACACACAUCACACUUACAACACUUAAGAACAUUCUCACGAUGACUGUUGAACUGGAAAAACUGAUCUUACCUAGCCAUAUGGCCUGCUGCCUCUGCCAAUUUAAAAAUAGCAUUGAGGCUGUCUGCAAGACAGUCAAGCUGCAUUGCAACACUGCAUGUCUGACUAACAGCAUACAUUGUCCUGAAGAAGCAUCUGUAGGGAAUCCAGAAGGAGCGUUCAUGAAGAUGUUACAAGCCCGGAAGCAGCACAUGAGCACUCAGCUGACUAUUGAGUCGGAGGCGCCCUCAGACAGCAGUGGCAUCAACUUGUCAGGCUUUGGGGGUGAUCAGCUUGAAAUUCAGCUAACCGAGCAGCUACGGUCCCUCAUCCCCAACGAGGAUGUGAGAAAGUUCAUGUCUCAUGUUAUCCGGACCUUGAAAAUGGAAUGUUCAGAAACACAUGUGCAAGGGAGCUGUGCCAAGCUCAUGUUGCGAACAGGCCUCCUGAUGAAGCUUCUCAGCGAGCAGCAGGAAGCAAAGGCAUUGAAUGUAGAAUGGGAUACGGACCAACAAAAAACAAAUUAUAUUAAUGAGAACAUGGAACAGAAUGAACAGAAAGAGCAGAAGUCAAGUGAGCUCAUGAAAGAAGUUCCAGGAGAUGACUAUAAGAACAAACUCAUCUUCGCAAUAUCUGUGACUGUAAUACUAAUAAUUUUGAUUAUAAUUUUUUGUCUUAUAGAGGUGAAUUCACAUAAAAGGGCAUCAGAAAAAUACAAAGACAACCCAUCAAUAUCAGGAGCCUGAGCAUGAGUUAAAGCAUGUGGAUGGCCUGGAGCUAUGUUUUUAAAAUUGUUAUUAAAUAUUGGUUUUUUACUUAAAUCAAUGAAAACUUUCUUUACUUUGUGGUUGUGUUCCUCAAAAUGAGAAUUUUUAACAAUAAUAAAAAUAAAGCUUGUUAGAUCA